GUCUCUCCCUGCAGCUGGAGCUCCAGGUCGUCUGUUCACUGCUCUCUGUCUUCUUCUCCUAGAGGCCCAGCCUCUGUGGCCCUGUGUCCUGCAGGUAUUGGGAGAUCCACAGCUAAGACGCCAGGACCCCCUGGAAGCCUAGAAAUGGGGCCAUUGCAAUUUAGAGAUGUGGCCAUAGAAUUCUCUCUGGAGGAGUGGCAUUGCCUGGACAUGGCACAGCGGAAUUUAUAUAGGGAUGUGAUGUUAGAGAACUACAGAAACCUGGUCUUUCUUGGUAUUGUUGUCUCAAAGCCAGACCUCAUCACCCAUCUGGAGCAAGGAAAAAAACCUUCGACUAUGCAGAGACAUGAGAUGGUAGCCAACCCCUCAGUUUUGUGUUCUCAUUUUAACCAAGACCUUUGGCCAGAGCAGAGCAUAAAAGAUUCUUUCCAAAAACUGAUACUGAGAAGACAUAAAAAAUGUGGACAUGAUAAUUUGCAGUUAAAAAAAGGCUGUGAAAGUGUGGAUAAGUGUAAAGUGCACAAAAGAGGUUAUAAUGGACUUAACCAAUGUUUGACAACUACCCAAAGCAAAAUGUUUCAAUGUGAUAAACAUGGGAAAGUCUUUCAUCAAUUUUCAAAUACAAACAGACAUAAGAUAAGACAUACUGGAAAAAACCCUUUCAAAUUUACAGAAUGUGGCAAAGCUUUUAACCGGUCCUCAACCCUUACUACACAUAAGAAAAUUCAUACUGGAGAGAAACCCUAUAAAUGUAUAGAAUGUGGCAAAGCCUUCAACCGGUCCUCACACCUUACUACACAUAAGAUAAUUCAUACUGGAGAGAAACGGUACAAAUGUGAAGACUGUGGCAAAGCCUUUAACCGCUCCUCUAACCUUACUACACAUAAGAAAAUUCAUACUGGAGAGAAACCCUACAAAUGUGAAGAAUGUGGCAAGGCCUUUAAGCGCUCCUCUAUCCUUACUACACAUAAGAGAAUUCAUACUGGAGAGAAACCCUACAAAUGUGAAGAAUGUGGCAAAGUUUUUAAGUACCUUUCUUCCCUUUCUACACAUAAGAUAAUUCAUACUGGAGAGAAACCCUACAAAUGUGAAGAAUGUGGUAAAGCCUUCAACUGGUCCUCACACCUUACUACACAUAAGAGAAUUCAUACUGGAGAGAAACCCUACAAAUGUGAAGAAUGUGGCAAAGGCUUUAAGUACUCCUCUACCCUUACUAAACAUAAAAUAAUCCAUACUGGAGAGAAACCCUACAAAUGUGAAGAAUGUGGUGAAGCCUUUAAGUACUCCUGUUCCCUUACUGCACAUAAGAUAAUUCAUACUGGAAAGAAACCUUACAAAUGUGAAGAAUGUGGCAAAGUGUUUAAGCACUCCUCUCCCCUUUCUAAACAUAAGAGAAUUCAUGCUGGAGAGAAACCCUACAAAUGUGAAGAAUGUGGCAAAGCCUUCAGUCGGUCCUCUAUUCUUACUACACAUAAGAUAAUUCACACUGGAGAGAAACCCUACGAAUGUGAAGACUGUGGCAAAGCCUUUAACCGCUCCUCUAACCUUACUAAACACAAGAAAAUUCAUACUGGAGAGAAGCCUUACAAAUGUGAAGAAUGUGGCAAGGCCUUUAAGUGCUCCUCUAUUCUUACUACACAUAAGAGAAUUCAUACUGCAGAUAAACCCUACAAAUGUGAAGAAUGUGGCAAAGACUUUAAGUACUCCUCUACCCUUACUAGACAUAAGAGAAUUCAUACUGGAGAGAAACCCUACAAAUGUGAAGAAUGUGGCAAAGCUUUUAAUCAUCCCGCAACCCUUUUUUCACAUAAGAAAAUUCAUACUGGAGGGAAACCACACAAGUGCAAUAAAUGUGGCAAAGCCUUUAUUUCAUCCUCAAACCUUAGUAGACAUGAGAUAAUUCAUAUGGGAGGGAAUCCCUACAAAUGUGAAAAUGUGGCAAAGCCUUAGACACUCCUCUACCCUUACUAGACAUAAGAUAAUUCAUACUGGAGAGAAACCCUAUGAGUUUGAUGAAUGUGGGAAAGACUUUAACCAGCUAUCAACUUUUACUAAAUAUGAGAAUUUAUGGAACACAAACACUACAAAUAUAAAGAAUGUGACAAAGCUUUUAGGAAGUUCUCAACCCUUAUUACACAUAAUUCAUACUGGAUAGAAACCCUACACCUGUGAAGAAUGUGGCAUAGCCUAUAACAAUUUUCAAUCAAUUCUUUUUUUUUUUUUGAGAUGAAGUUUCAUGCUUGUCACCCAAGCUGGAAUACAAUGUGAUGAUCUCGGAUCACUGAAACCUCUGCCUCCCGGGUUCAAGCCAUUUUCCUGCCUCAGCUUGUCUAGUAGAUGAGAUUAUGGGGGGUGGAGCCAAGAUGGCUGAAUAGGUACAGCUCCUGUCUACAGCUCCCAGCCUGAGUGACGCAGAAGAUGGGUGAUUUCUGCAUUUCCGUCUGAUGUACCAGGUUCAUCUCACUAGGGGGUGCCAGACAGUGGCUGCAGGACAGUGGAUGCAGUGCACUGUGCAUGAGCCGAAGCAGGGCGAGGCAUUGCCUCACUCACGAAGCGCAAGGAGUCAGGGAGUUCCCUUUCCUAGUCAAAGAAAGGGGUGACAGAUGGCACCUGGAAAAUCGGGUCACUCCCACCCUAAUACUGCGCAAUUCCAAUGGGCUUAAAAAAUGGCACACCAGAUUAUAUCCUGCACCUGGCUCAGAGGGUCCUAUGCCCAUGGAGUCUCACUGAUUGCUAGCACAGCAGUCUGAGAUCAAACUGCAAGGCAGCAGCGAGGCUGGGGGAGGAGUGCCUGCCAUUGCCCAGGCUUGCUUAGGUAAAGCAGCUGGGAAGCUAGAACUGGGUGGAGCCCACCACAGCUCAAGGAGGCCUGCCUGCCUCUGUAGGCUCCACCUCUGGGGGCAGGGCACAGACAAAAAGACAGCAGUAACCUCUGCAGACUUAAACGUCCCUGUCUGACAGCUUUGAAGAGAGUAGUGGUUCUCCCAGCACGCAGCUGGAGAUCUGAGAACGGGCAGACUGCCUCCUCAAGUGGGUCUCUGACCCCCGAGCAGCCUAACUGGGAGGCACCCCCCAGUAGGGGCAGACUGACACUUCACACGGCUGGGUACUCCUCACACAAAACUUCCAGAGGACCGAUCAGGCAGCAGCAUUUGCGGUUCAUGAAAAUCCGCUGUUCUACAGCCACUGAUGCUGAUACCCAGGCAAACAGUGUCUGGAGUGGACCUCUAGCAAAUUCCAACAGACCUGCAGCUGAGGGUCCUGUCUGUUAGAAGGAAAACUAACAAACAGAAAGGACAUCCACACCAAAAACCCAUCUGUACAUCACCAUCAUCAAAGACCAAAAGUAGAUAAAACCACAAAGAUGGGGAAAAAACAGAGCAGAAAAACUGAAAAGUCUAAAAAGCAGAGCACCUCUCCUCCAAAGGAAUGCAGUUCCCCACCAGCAACAGAACAAAGCUGGAUGGAGAAUGACUUUGAUGAGUUGAGAGAAGAAGGCUUCAGACGAUCAAACUACUCCGAGCUACAGGAGGAAAUUCAAACCAAAGGCAAAGAAGUUAAAAACUUUGAAAAAAAAUUAGACGAAUGUAUAACUAGAAUAACCAAUGCAGAGAAAUGCUUAAAGGACCUGAUGGAGCUGAAAGCCAAGGAUCAAGAACUAUGUGAAGAAUGCAGAAGCCUCAGGAGCCAAUGCGAUCAACUGGAAGAAAGGGUAUCAGUGAUGGAAGAUGAAAUGAAUGAAAUGAAGUGAGAAGGGAAGUUUAGAGAAAAAAAAUUAAAAAGAAACAAACAAAGUCUCCAAGAAAUAUGGGACUAUGUGAAAAGACCAAAUCUACCUCUGAUUGGUGUACCUGAAAGUGAGGGGGAAAAUGGAACCAACUUGGAAAACACUCUGCAGGAUAUUAUCCAGGAGAACUUCCCCAAUCUAGCAAGGCAGGCCGACAUUCAGAUUCAGGAAAUACAGAGAACGCCACAAAGAUACUCCUUGAGAAGAGCAACUCCAAGACACAUAAUUGUCAGAUUCACCAAAGUUGAAAUGAAGGAAAAAAUGUUAAGGGCAGCCAGAGAGAAAGGUCGGGUUACCCACAAAGGGAAGCCCAUCAGACUCACAGCUGACCUCUUGGCAGAAACUCUAUAAGCCAGAAGAGAGUGGGGGCCAAUAUUCAACAUUCUUAAAGAAAAGAAUUUUCAACCCAGAAUUUCAUAUCCAGCCAAACUAAGCUUCAUAAGUGAAGGAGAAAUAAAAUACUUUACAGACAAGCAAAUGCUGAGAGAUUUUGUCACCACCAGGCCUGCCCUAAAAGAGCUCCUGAAGGAAGCACUAAACAUGGAAAGGAACAACUGAUACCAGCCGCUGCAAAAUCAUGCCAAAAUGUAAAGACCAUCGAGACUAGGAAGAAACUGCAUGAACUAACGAGCAAAAUAACCAGCUAACAUCAUAAUGACAGGAUCAAAUUCUCACAUAACAAUAUUAGCUUUAAAUGUAAAUGGGCUAAAUGCUCCAAUUAAAAGACACAGACAGGCAAAUUGGAUAAAGAGUCAAGACCCAUCAGUGUGCUGUAUUCAGGAAACCCAUCUCACGUGCAGAGACACACAUAGGCUCAAAAUAAAAGGAUGGAGGAAGAUCUACGAAGCAAAUGGAAAACAAACAAAAAAAGAGGCAUGGGUUGCAAUCCUAGUCUCUGAUAAAACAGAAUUUAAACCAACAAAGAUCAAAAGAGACAAUGCCAUUACAUAAUGGUAAAUGGAUCAAUUCAACAAGAAGAGAUAACUAUCCUAAAUAUAUAUGCACCCAAUACAGGAGCACUCAGAUUCAUAAAGCAAGUCCUGAGUGACUUACAAAGAGACUUACACUCCCACACAAUAAUAAUGGGAGACUUAAACACCCCACUGUCAACAUUAGACAGAUCAAUGAGACAGAAAGUUAACAAGGAUAUCCAGGAAUUGAACACAGCUCUGCACCAAGCGGACCUAAUAGACAUCUACAGAACUCUCCACCCCAAAUUAACAGAAUAUACAUUUUUUUCAGCACCACACCACACCUAUUCCAAAAUUGACCACAUAGUUGGAAGUAAAGCACUCCUCAGCAAAUGUAAAGGAACAAAAAUUAUAAGAAACUGUCUCUCAGACCACAGUGCAAUCAAACUAGAACUCAGGAUUAAGAAACUCACUCAAAACUGCUCAACUACAUGGAAACUGAACAACCUGCUCCUGAAUGACUACUGGGUACAUAAUGAAAUGAAGGCAGGAAUAAAGAUGUUCUUUGAAACCAAUGAGAACAAAGACACAACAUACCUGAAUCUCUGAGACACAUUCAAAGCAGUGUGUAGAGGGAAAUUUAUAGCACUAAAUGCCCACAAGAGAAAGCAGGAAAGAUCCAAAAUUAACACCCUAACAUCACAAUUAAAAGAACUAGAAUUGCAAGAGCAAACACAGUCAAAAACUAGCAGAAGGCAAGAAAUAACUAAAAUCAGAGCAGAACUCAAGGAAAUAGAGACACAAAAAACCCUUCAAAAAAUUAAUGUAUCCAGGAGCUGGUUUUUUGAAAGGAUCAACAAAAUUGAUAGACCGCUAGCAAGACUAAUGAAGAAAAGAGAGAAGAAUCAAAUAGAUGCAAUAAAAAAUGAUAAAGGGAGUAUCAUCACUGAUCCCACAGAAAUACAAACUACCAUCAGAGAAUACUACAAACACCUCUACGCAAAUAAACUAGAAAAUCUAGAAGAAAUGGAUACAUUCCUCAACACAUACACCCUCCCAAGACUAAACCAGGAAGAAGUUGAAUCUCUGAAUAGACCAAUAACAGCCUCUGGGGUUGAGGUGAUAAUCAAUAGCUUACCAACCAAAAAGAGUCCAGGACCAGGUGGAUUCACAGCCGAAUUCUACCAGAGGUACAAGGAGGAGCUGGUACUAUUCCUUCUGAAACUAUUCCAAUCAAUAGGAAAAGAGGGAAUCCUCCCUAACUCAUUUUAUGAGGCCAGCAUCUUCCUGAUACCAAAGCUGGGCAGAGACACAACCAAAAAAGAGAAUUUUAGACCAAUAUCCUUGAUGAACAUUGAUGUGAAAAUCCUCAAUAAAAUACUGGCAAACCGAAUCCAGCAGCACAUCAAAAAGCUUAUCCACCAUGAUCAAGUGGGCUUCAUCCCUGGGAUGCAAGGCUGGUUCAACAUACGCAAAUCAAUAAAUGUAAUCCAGUAUAUAAACAGAACCAAAGGCAGAAACCACAUGAUUAUCUCAAUAGAUGCAGAAAAGGCCUUUGACAAAAUUCAACAACACUUCAUGCUAAAAACUCUCAAUAAAUUAGGUAUUGAUGGGAUGUAUCUCAAAAUAAUAAGAACUAUCUAUGACAAGCCCACGGCCAAUAUCAUACUGAAUGGGCAAAAACUGGAAGCAUUCCCUUUGAAAACUGGCACAAGACAGGAUGCCCUCUCUCACCACUCCUAUUCAACAUAUUGUUGGAAGUUCUGGCCAGGGCAAUGAGGCAGGAGAAGAAAAUAAAGGGUAUUCAAUUAGGAAAAGAGGAGGUCAAAUUGUCCCUGUUUGCAGAUGACAUGAUUGUAUAUCUAGAAAACCCCAUUGUCUCAGCCCAAAAUCUCCUUAAGCUGAUAAGCAACUUCAGCAAAGUCUCAGGAUACAAAAUCAAUGUACAAAAAUCACAAGCAUUCUUAUAUACCAAUAACAGACAGAGAGCCAAAUCAUGAAUAAACUCCCAUUCACAAUUGCAUCAAAGAGAAUAAAAUACCUAGGAAUCCACCUUACAAGGGAUGUGAAGGACCUCUUCAAGGAGAACUACAAACCACUGCUUAACGAAAUAAAAGAGGAUGCAAAGAAAUGGAAGAACAUUCCAUGCUCAUGGGUAGGAAGAAUCAAUAUCAUGAAAAUGGCCCAUACUGCCCAAGGUAAUUUAUAGAUUCAAUGCCAUCCCCAUCAAGCUACCAAUGACUUUCUUCACAGAAUUGAAAAACACUACUUUAAAGUUCAUAUGGAACCAAAAAAGAGCCCACAUUGCCCAGUCAAUCCUAAGCCAAAUGAAUAAAGCCGGAGGCAUCACGCUACCUGACUUCAAACUAUGCUACAAGGCUACAUAACCAAAAUAGCAUGGUACUGGUACCAAAACAGAGAUAUAGAUCAAUAGAACAGAACAGAGCCCUCAGAAAUAAUGCCACAUAUCUACAACUAUCUGACCUUUGACAAACCUGACAAAAAAGCAAUGGGGAAAGCAUUCCCUAUUUAAUAAAUGAUGCUGGGAAAACUGUCUAGCCAUAUGUAGAAAGCUGAAACUGGAUCCCUUCCUUACACCUUAUACAAAAAUUAAUUCAAGAUGGAUUAAAGACUUACAUGUUAGACCUAAAACCAUAAAAACCCUAGAAGAAAACCUAGGCAAUACCAUUCAGGACAUAGGCAUGGGCAAGGACUUCAUGUCUAAAACACCAAAAGCAAUGGCAACAAAAGCCAAAAUUGACAAAUGGGAUCUAAUUAAACUAAAGACCUUCUGCACAGCAAAAGAAACUACCAUCAGAGUCAACAGGCAACCUACAAAAUGGGAGAAAAUUUUCGCAACCUACUCAUCUGACAAAGGGCUAAUAUCCAGAAUCUACAAUGAACUCAAACAAAUUUACAGGAACAAACAACCCCAUCAAAAAGUCGGCAAAGGACAUGAACAGACACUUCUCAAAAGAAGACAUUUAUGCAGCCAAAAAACACAUGAAAAAAUGCUCACCAUCACUGGCCAUCAGAGAAAUGCAAAUCAAAACCACAAUGAGAUACCAUCUCACACCAGUUAGAAUGGCAAUCAUUAAAAACUCAGGAAACAACAGGUGCUGGAGAGGAUGUGGAGAAAUACGAACACUUUUACACUGUUGGUGGGACUGUAAACUAGUUCAACCAUUGUGGAAGUCAGUGUGGCGAUUCCUCAGGGAGCUAGAACUAGAAAUACCAUUUGACCCAGCCAUCCCAUUACUGGGUAUAUACCCAAAGGACUAUAAAUCGUGCUGCUAUAAAGACAAAUGCACACGUAUGUUUAUUGCGGCACUAUUCACAAUAGCAAAGACUUGGAACCAACCCAAAUGUCCAACAACGAUAGACUGGAUUAAGAAAAUGUGGCACAUAUACAACAUGGAAUACUAUGCAGCCAUAAAAAUGAUGAGUUCAUGUCCUUUGUAGGGUCAUGGAUGAAACUGGAAAUCAUCAUUCUCAGCAAACUAUCGCAAGGACAGAAAACCGAACACUGCAUGUUCUCACUCAUAGGUGAGAAUUGCACAUUGAGAACACAUGGACACAGGAAGGGGAACAUCACACUCCGGGGACUGUUGUGGGUUGGGGGGAGGGGGGAGGGAUAGCAUUAGGAGAUACACCUAAUGCUAAAUGAUGAGUUAAUGGGUGCAGUACACCAACAUGGCACAUGUAUACAUAUGUAACAAACCUGCACAUUGUGCACAUGUACCCUAAAACUUAAAGUACAAUAAUAAUAAAAUAAAAAAAUUAAAAAAGAUUA